AGUAAGAGGGUGGCAGGUUGGGCCAGGCCAGAGCCUGGACCUGGGAUCAGGAAGGGGUUGCAGGGAGGGAUGGAGGGGCUGAAAACCCUGGGCCCCUGCGGCCACCCCCACCCCCAGUGUCCCCCAACCCCAGCCUCCAGCAGCCAUGGAGGAGGCCUGGACCAGCCCUGCCAGGGAUUUGUAGGGUGGCCCUGCCUGGGCCCCAUCUCCUCUGCUCACUCAGUGCAGUCCCAGAGACCUUUCCCAGUCCCAGGGGCAGGGGGCAGUGGGCCCACAGUGGAGGGCGAGGCUCCCGGGCUCUUUCUGUCCAGCCAGGAGCAGAGAGCGAGAGACACUGAGGGGCCGAGACAAGGAGACCUGGAGGCAGGGCUUGGGUGGGGCUGGCCCCUGCACCCAGGGUCGAACCAGGGGGCUCCCAGGCAGGGGGGAUCCAUUGGCUCAGGGACCAGACCCUGCCCAUGCCCACCCCUGUCACGGGAGGGAGGGGCCCUGGCCUCGCCCAGGGUAGCCCUGUCCCAGCUUCAGUGCGGGCUGCUGGGCUCUGCAGAACAGUCCUUCCUGCAGCUGGAGCAGGAGAACCACAGCCUGAAAAGGCAGAAUCAGGAACUUCGGGAGCAGCUGGGGGCCCUCCUGGGGCCGGGGCAGCAGUUCCUGCCCCUGUGUCCCGAACACUCAAGCUGCACUGCUCUGGCCUGGCCCCCCGACCCGGCUGGCACGCAGCCCUUGGGGAACAGGGCACCUCUGCAGCUGCUGCGGCGGGAGCUGUGCCAGGGGCAAGAGGCUUUCGUGCAACAGUCCCAGGUGGGCCUGGGGGAGGGGCUGUGGGGGGGGAGGAAGCUUCGUAACAGCACUCCAGGUGGGCCUGAGGGAUUCAUUAGGGAGGGAGGUCUUCGUGCAGUAGGCCAGUGGGCCCAGCGGGGAGGUACUGGCCACCCUGCUGAUGCUGCCCAAGCCCAUCCUGGGCCCCACCCUCAGAACGAGCUGCAGCAGAUCCGCCUGUGCUUUGAGAGGAAGAAGAUGGUCAUCACAGAGGUGUGGGACAACGUGGCUGAGAUGCACAUGGCCCUGAACAACCAGGCCACCGGGCUCCUGAACCUCAAGAAGGACAUCCGGGGCGUGCUGGACCAGAUGGAGGACAUCCAGCUGGAGAUUCUCAGGGAGCGGGCCCAGUGCCGCACUCGAGCCAGGAAGGAGAAGCAGAUGGCAAGCAUGUCGAAAGGGAGGCCAAAGCUGGGAAGCUCCAAGGGCCUGGCAGGCCAGCUCUGGCUGCUGACCCUGAGGCUGCUGCUGGGCGCCCUGCUGGUCUGGACCGCUGCCUACGUGUACGUGGUGAACCCCACACCUUUCGAGGGGCUGGUGCCACCCCUGCUGAGCCGUGCCACCGUCUGGAAGCUCCGGGCCCUGCUGGACCCCUUCCUGCGCCUCAAAGUGGACGGCUUCCUGCCCUUCUAGGCCAGAGGCCCAGCGGCCCCAGCAAGGAGGCCAGGCGACCAGCACUGCCCCGGAUGCCCAGUGGCCGUGCCAGCCCCCUGCACAUGGCACCACUGUGCACCAUCCUUGCCAGAAGCUGCAGAGAAGGGUGGAGGUGGGGUCUGUCCUGAGGGCUGGGCCUGUGGCUGGACAUAGAAUCAUGACAUAAGUGGCCGGUGA